GGCUCUGUUAGAGUCUACAGAAAAUUCUCUCUUAAUAAGAGGACCUUCGGAAUGACAAGCCCUCCUCUUACCCCACAUAGAACAAUUCCAAAGCAAAUCGACUUUUGCGUUUUACCUCUGGGAUUAGAUAGAAUAAGGGGGCAGAGUGGAAACGAGAGCCAAAAUUGUGGGGCUGCAUCUCCAGAGAAGGUGAUGAUUCUGUUGAAGUUGGAGGUUCCCGGGGAAUCUAUAACUUCCUGUCUUUUUAACAGGUUGAGAUCCGUAGCAUUUUAGUGUCCGAGAGGAUAAUUGCUAAGGGAGCAGAGACCUCUUCACACCUUCAUGCGCUUAGACCUGCCUAGAGGCUCAGAUGGCUCAGUGGCACUGCUCACAGAGAACACAGGCUGGAGGACAUGGAGUCGGGGAACGGCUGGCCCAGUGCCAGGACCAGAGUAGUCGGCAUGCUGCUGAGCUGCGGGACUUCAAGAACAAGAUGCUGCCACUGCUGGAGGUGGCAGAGAAGGAGCGGGAGGCACUCAGAACUGAGGCCGACACCAUCUCCGGGAGAGUGGAUCGUCUGGAGCGGGAGGUAGACUAUCUGGAGACCCAGAACCCAGCUCUGCCCUGUGUAGAGUUUGAUGAGAAGGUGACUGGAGGCCCUGGGACCAAAGGCAAGGGAAGAAGGAAUGAGAAGUACGAUAUGGUGACAGACUGUGGCUACACAAUCUCUCAAGUGAGAUCAAUGAAGAUUCUGAAGCGAUUUGGUGGCCCAGCUGGUCUAUGGACCAAGGAUCCACUGGGGCAAACAGAGAAGAUCUACGUGUUAGAUGGGACACAGAAUGACACAGCCUUUGUCUUCCCAAGGCUGCGUGACUUCACCCUUGCCAUGGCUGCCCGGAAAGCUUCCCGAGUCCGGGUGCCCUUCCCCUGGGUAGGCACAGGGCAGCUGGUAUAUGGUGGCUUUCUUUAUUUUGCUCGGAGGCCUCCUGGAAGACCUGGUGGAGGUGGUGAGAUGGAGAACACUUUGCAGCUAAUCAAAUUCCACCUGGCAAACCGAACAGUGGUGGACAGCUCAGUAUUCCCAGCAGAGGGGCUGAUCCCCCCCUACGGCUUGACAGCAGACACCUACAUCGACCUGGCAGCUGAUGAGGAAGGUCUUUGGGCUGUCUAUGCCACCCGGGAGGAUGACAGGCACUUGUGUCUGGCCAAGUUAGAUCCACAGACACUGGACACAGAGCAGCAGUGGGACACACCAUGUCCCAGAGAGAAUGCUGAGGCUGCCUUUGUCAUCUGUGGGACCCUCUAUGUCGUCUAUAACACCCGUCCUGCCAGUCGGGCCCGCAUCCAGUGCUCCUUUGAUGCCAGCGGCACCCUGACCCCUGAACGGGCAGCACUCCCUUAUUUUCCCCGCAGAUAUGGUGCCCAUGCCAGCCUCCGCUAUAACCCCCGAGAACGCCAGCUCUAUGCCUGGGAUGAUGGCUACCAGAUUGUCUAUAAGCUGGAGAUGAGGAAGAAAGAGGAGGAGGUUUGAGGAGCUAGCCUUGUUUUUUGCAUCUUUCUCACUCCCAUACAUUUAUAUUAUAUCCCCACUAAAUUUCUUGUUCCUCAUUCUUCAAAUGUGGGCCAGUUGUGGCUCAAAUCCUCUAUAUUUUUAGCCAAUGGCAAUCAAAUUCUUUCAGCUCCUUUGUUUCAUACGGAACUCCAGAUCCUGAGUAAUCCUUUUAGAGCCCGAAGAGUCAAAACCCUCAAUGUUCCCUCCUGCUCUCCUGCCCCAUGUCAACAAAUUUCAGGCUAAGGAUGCCCCAGACCCAGGGCUCUAACCUUGUAUGCGGGCAGGCCCAGGGAGCAGGCAGCAGUGUUCUUCCCCUCAGAGUGACUUGGGGAGGGAGAAAUAGGAGGAGACGUCCAGCUCUGUCCUCUCUUCCUCACUCCUCCCUUCAGUGUCCUGAGGAACAGGACUUUCUCCACAUUGUUUUGUAUUGCAACAUUUUGCAUUAAAAGGAAAAUCCACUGCU